AGGUCUCAGUAGGCUGGGAUCAUGCCACUGCGCUCCAGCCUGGGCAACACAGCAAGACUCUGUCUCAAAGAAAAUUUUGUGGAACACCUAUUUUCUCACUGACAUGAAAAAUGUUUCAAAGAUGAAUAAUGUCCAUCAAGCUAUGGCAAUGGAAGUGAGGAUGAUAAAGGAUUGCACAGUUGUUCACAACCUCACUGUUAGUAUCCUGCUGAGAUAGUUGGUCUCCUCAUCACUGUAGCAUCUUUUAUGUACAGCAGAGGGCAGAAGCUCCUUGGCAUGUAUGUGAGGGAACCACAUAUAUGGAAGGCUGUUAUUCCUGAGAAAGGAGGAUGUGCAGACACUCACAGAACAAAGCCUUUGUAAAGGAAAGGCGGCCGAUGAGAUGGAGUGCUUCCUUCACCUGUGGUGGGUCUGUAUCCAUGAAAUCGCCCACUCACAAUCGCUUUUUGUAGCUACUGGAAGCACUAGGCGUCUGACCUGCCAUCAUCCUUGUUAUGAUGUCAUAAUCAUAUUCUGUCCGUGUUUAUUGCAGUUCUCUGGUUUGUCUGGAGUGUUUGCAAGUCAGUCAUCAUAGUGGCAGCUUCCGCCUGCUACAGGAUAUUUAUAUAUGGAAGCAUACCAUGGCAGGAGUGCUGGAAAGGUGGUGUCAGCUAACAGUUGCUUCAGCCAGAUAAGGACGGUAACUUCAGUCCAAUAAAAACCUCAUCAGUUACCAACUAAAUCAGGGCAUGGUGUUUUUUUGUUGUUUUCUUUUUAAAGCAUAGUUUUAGUAAUAUAUUUACUAAAAACCUUAGACAUUAUGAAAAAAGUCAGGAUUUGGAAUCUUACACUGCUUGGCUAAAUUGACACAAUAUAGACCAACAGUUUCAUCCUGGGGCUUAUGGGUCUCAUAGGAGCACCCGUAUGCUGAAGAAAGGCAAAGAGAGAACUACAGAAUUUGUAGAAAAGUUUUGUUGUAGUUGCUUCUGAACAAUUAGUUUUUGUUUGUUUGUUUUGUUUUGUUUUGUUUUUCUGGUAACCUAGCAGUCAAAGCUCACAUUUUUGUAAGUAAUUUGCAUGCUAUUACUCUACUGAGACUGAAUUAUGAUUCUCGAGUCUGGGAAGUUUUUGUUGCAUGUGCUCUGUGUUUUUCAUUUUUGAUAGAAAUGAUUUAGACUUGAUUUUAAAAAUUACUUCCUGAAUGUGAAGAGGCAUUGACUGGGAAAUGAAAUUAAAGAACAAAUUACCAUGACUCAUUCAAUAACACUGCUUAUUAGCUUUGAAUUAUGCCCUAUUAUAACAAUUCUGAUUUUGUGGCAAGCAAUACUGGUGUGAGUUAUUUCUGUGGUUUGAUACCAAGCACCUGCCUGGUUAAAAAAUAAAGCACCAGGCAAUUUUUCAUAGACAAUUAUCUUUAUUUGUUGGAAUAUUUAUUUGUAAAUAGUCAAAGAAUUCUUAAAUGACAAAAAAUCAACUGUUAGCAGUGAUCUAAACCAGAGGAAAAUGAAAUUACUUACAUGUUUCCAGUCAAGGUAUAAGAAAGGGUUCUGUUAAAGGGAUGCUGCUUUAGCCAAUCUUGGUGAAUAAGCAAAUUUGCACACUGGAGUUGAAAGGAGGGUCAAGUUAGUGUGAUGAAGAAUUGCUAGUAACACUGGCUUCUCCAGCCUUGCUGGUUGUUCCUAGAUGCCCUCAUUUGGAGAUGCCAAAGAUAGCAACUACUGGGUGUCAAACAGCCGUGGGGCCUGGUUUUAAGGCCAUGUGAUCUUGUAUCCCUUUACUAGCAGCCUCAUGAGUCAUUUGCAAGUCAUUUGCAGGCUCUUGGAGCCCUGGAACAGCACCCAACUCAGUUUUCUCUGCUAGUUCUUUAUUUUUCCAUUUGCGUGUUGCAGCUCAUUAAAAAAAUAUUGGAAUAGCAUAUAUUUACAUUGUGACUUCACUCUAAAGAAGACAUUUUCUUUCAAAGCACGUCAUGGCUCACUAGGUUGUUGUCUUAGUUUUUUUUGGAGUCACCUUUUGAGUAGAUAGCAAGACCAGUAAUAUGGAGAUUUUAUUAGCUGUACUCUUAAAGUCAGUUUUUGUGGCCAUGAUUUUCUAGCUAGGUCUCUAUUUUGUAAACAUUGAUUAAGCCUCAGUAUGAAAUUGAAGCAACAGCAGAUACAUUCCUGAAGGGGAAGCUAAGGCUCAAGGCUAUUAAGUCAGAGAUCCAAAAAUGAACCAUGCUUCAGUUACCACACCUAAAAUAGAAGCUGUGUGCAGAACAGUGGUCCUGUGAUGUGACACAUAAAACUUUUUUUCCUGGUCACAUAUUACUGUUUGGUCAAAUAUUAGUAUAAAUGGAUGAUAAAAUAUGAAACACAUCUAAAAGAAUUGUUUUAAAAUCUGUGACUAUGCAUGAGUGAAUAUUUUGGGGCCUUGGUUUUAACUGCAAAAGGAUAAGAUUUGACUGACCUCUAAGGCCCUUUUACUCUAUUUGCUGCUGCUUUUUAAUUUUUUUUAAUUGUCAUAUCAAGUCAUUUCCUUAGGAAUGCUCUAUGAAGUAUAUUUGGAAUUCAGUAAUGUCAAUAAAGUGCUAUGGUAGUAUCUUAUCUGAAAACUCAGGGAAUUGUUUGUUCUUGUUAAUUAAAAUUUCAAGAUAAGUGAAACACACUUUUUUAGUUUUAACCCUAAAAAAAAUUUUUAGUCCAUGACUUUUUGAGCUCACUUUCUUAGCUAGGGUUCUGGUAGCACAUUUUUCACAAGUACCAGUAGUUUUAGGUAUUACUGGGAAAUUGUUUUUUUAAUAUUUUAGACUAAGUUUAAAUUGCUCAGUAAGUGUCUGAUACUUUUUUUCCCCACAUCUUCUUUAGGUGUAUACUUUUUUUUUUUUUUUAUGAAUUUGGUUUCUCCCAACUCUAUAUUGCUCUUCAUUCUGUAGAUGAGUUUUAAAGGAAAUUUUUGCAACAACAGAAAGUAAACAGUGUGUUGUCAAAUACACACAGGCACCAUAUUUAUCGCAUUGACUUUACUAGAGUCCAGAUAGACAUCACAUGAGGAUUUUUAUCCUCAAUCUUAUUUCUGUUCAUGUACUUAUUAUUAACUGCCUCCAAUUCUUUUGAAAAUGGUGAGAUUUAAAUCCUAAAUAAACAUUUCAGGUGUUCCAUCUUAACAUAAGUCACCAACUUCUAAACCUGGCACUGGGCAUUUGAAGAAUAGGAUUCGUCCCUACUCUAAGGAGUUUUCAGUCUAUCGGGAAAUCAAAGAUGUAAGCAAAUAGAUGCAAUAAAAUACUACAGAUGUUCUGAUAGAAGAAUGUAAAGAAUCCAGCAAAGGCAAAAGGAAAGACAGGUUGGUUCUCUCUUCCUAGGGGAAGUGAUGUUUGAGCUGAGUCUUGAGGCAGGAUUAGGAAGGGAUAUAGAAAAGAAAAGUAGCACAAAGCAAGACUCAUUGAAUGCUGAACAAAAGGCCCGAUUCCAGCUCUGCUGCCAGGCAAAUGUGUGAUCCUGGGCAUUUACCUCGCCGAGCUUCCAUUUCCUCAUUUGCGGAAAGGAUGGGAACUAAAGCACAUCUAACACCCUUUCUAGAUCCAAACAUCCUCUAUCACGAUUAGACUUGAUAACCAUGAAAGGAAAAGCUUUUAUAGUAAUUGAAAUUUGUCUUUCUAGAGGCUUCUUUUCACAUAAUUAAAUGGCCACAAGUUCUCUGUUGUGCUAGAGAUACAUCUCCACAUAAACCUUUUAAACUCUUCAGGAUUUUCAGUGUUGCUUGCAGUUGUGCUGUCGUUAGAGAAUAUUACUUUCAAUAUUUAAUAAACCUCAAGCUAUUACAUAAGUGACCUCAGUCUAAGGGAAACCCAGGUGGAAGAGAUCUCAGAGGUCCUGAAGUCUAGCAGCAUUCCUCUCUAUAGCAGCUAAGUUUGCUAAGAUUGUUGUCUUGGGGACUCACAGUCAGCAUCUUAUGGCUAAAGGAAUUGUGUGAAGAGAAGGACUUACAUGCCAUAUGGAGGGAGGCUAUAAAAAUUGCAAUUUUCUAUUAAAGCCUCCUGCAAUUAGAAUGGUUCAUGGUAAUAUUCUCUUUUUUCAGAAUGUUUUGUGGCCACUGCUGACUAGCUUAAUUUUGUCUACCUAGUCUUCUUGCACAAAGGAUUUGAGGCAUCUCACCAGAAUGUGAACAAUGUAAUAAAAGAAAAAUUUUAAAAUUAGUUACAAAAUAAAAACAGAUCCAGGGAAAAUAUAGGCAGAACUGAGACAUCUGAGGAGGAGAAAAGAGUGUUUGCAGAUAAGCAGGGUAUACAUGGAUGUACAAUUCUUAAAAUUGGGCCACACAUUUGACUGUGAGCUUCCUGGCAAGCAAAGCAAAAAGAACGAUUACAAAGUGGUCCACAGAAGGAAAUAUUUUUUUCUGGAUAAGCCAAGUUCUCUAGAGCCUUAGUUGAAAAUACUAUUUGUGGGUGGUUCUUCAUAGGCCUGUCUGGCUUCCUGGUGGCUGUGGUUCUUGUGAAGUUGAGUUCACAAGCCCAACCUCUUGUUUUUAACAUCAGUGUUUUCUUCCAGGGACAAUGACUCAUUCUUCCCAGGACACUGGUUCUUGUGGCAUUCAGGAAGAUGGAAAGCUUUAUGUGGUGGAUUCCAUAAAUGACUUAAACAAACUAAACCUCUGUCCAGCCGGAUCGCAGCAUCUGUUCCCUCUAGAGGACAAAAUCCCAGUCCUUGGCACAAACUCAGGAAAUGGAAGCCGGAGUCUGUUUUUUGUGGGGCUGCUAAUUGUGCUGAUUGUCAGCCUGGCACUGGUUUUUUUCGUGAUAUUUCUAAUAGUUCAAACUGGAAACAAGAUGGAUGAUGUGUCAAGAAGACUAACAGCUGAAGGAAAAGACAUAGAUGAUCUUAAGAGAAUCAAUAACAUGAUCGUAAAGCGACUCAACCAACUCAACCAACUGGACUCUGAACAAAACUAAAGGAAUGAUUUUCUGAAAGCACCUGCUAACACCUUGAGCUUUUUACUUUCCUGGGAGUGUACAGGGUUAGGAACUGAGAAAGUGCACUUCCUCAGGCAACAGAUGAUCUGGUCAGGCAACCCACCCCUGGGGCCCACUUUCUGCAGCAAGAUGGGAGCAAUUCCAAGGCAAGUGGGUAUGGGAAUAGCAACUAAAAAGGGGUGAACUUGUCUCAGCCCCCUUUUAUGGUAGGGCACUUCAACUUUAAUGGGGUGGGCGGCUAGCAGGGAGGAGAAUCAACAAAGCAAGAGAACUUGACUAUGUACGUCCAACUUCUUACAGAAGGAGCUUUGCUACCAGAACAAGUUCACUGUGUCAAUGAAGUUCAUGACACCUCAUGCACCUUUACAGAUAUCUGGGAAAGCCUGAGAAAUUCAUUGAGUUUUAUGUAUUGAAGGGAACCAGGUGAUUACUCUUUUCAAUAAGAGGGAUUCUGCUCAGGUGAUUAGACUUUGACUCUAUUUCCCCAGGGACAGUGAUGGGUGGGCCCCAGAGCUAGUUGCUGUCUGGUGUUUGCUGGUGAAAACAUGAGCAGUAGUUAUGUGGGGCUGAGAGUCAAAAGGGAAAGCCUAAUUAAUUCAACUAAUGUUUAUUAAGCUCCUACUCUGUGCAAAUCACUCUACUCAAGAGGAGCUCACAUAAGAGUGCAGGAUAAAGAAAGGAGAUGGACAGUUAUAUGUAAUUAUAUAAACUUUGUGUAUUUUGUUUCUCAUGAAAAAACCCCUUUGGCACCCUGCUGAUUGAUUUGGAAGAAAUCUGAUAGAUUUGUGGCCUUUCCUAAAUUGCACUAGGAAAUUAUGUAGUUAGAAUAUUUGGAACCUGCAUUAGUUCCAGCAAUGAAAGUAAGACACACAGCAUAUGACAUAAGACACAGUGUGAAAUAAAUGAGUUUAAAAAGCAUAUGAGUCUUAGAAAAUCUUUUAUUUAAUAUAAAAAUAUUCUACCGGUCAAUUGAAGAAUGUAUUAUGAUUCUAUCAUUUUGGAUUGAUCAAAAACAUUUGGGUUUACUACGAUAUUAAGCAUUCACUUUACAAUACUAAAUAGUUAAUGAAAUAAACACAUUUUGCUUACCCA